AUCUCUAGAGCCGGCCCUGGCUCUCUGGCGCGGGGCCCCUUAGUCCGGGCUUUUUGCCAUGGGGUCUCUGUUCCCUCUGUCGCUGCUGUUUUUUUUGGCGGCCGCCUACCCGGGAGUUGGGAGCGCGCUGGGACGCCGGACUAAGCGGGCGCAAAGCCCCAAGGGUAGCCCUCUCGCGCCCUCCGGGACCUCAGUGCCCUUCUGGGUGCGCAUGAGCCCGGAGUUCGUGGCUGUGCAGCCGGGGAAGUCAGUGCAGCUCAAUUGCAGCAACAGCUGUCCCCAGCCGCAGAAUUCCAGCCUCCGCACCCCGCUGCGGCAAGGCAAGACGCUCAGAGGGCCGGGUUGGGUGUCUUACCAGCUGCUCGACGUGAGGGCCUGGAGCUCCCUCGCGCACUGCCUCGUGACCUGCGCAGGAAAAACACGCUGGGCCACCUCCAGGAUCACCGCCUACAAACCGCCCCACAGCGUGAUUUUGGAGCCUCCGGUCUUAAAGGGCAGGAAAUACACUUUGCGCUGCCACGUGACGCAGGUGUUCCCGGUGGGCUACUUGGUGGUGACCCUGAGGCAUGGAAGCCGGGUCAUCUAUUCCGAAAGCCUGGAGCGCUUCACCGGCCUGGAUCUGGCCAACGUGACCUUGACCUACGAGUUUGCUGCUGGACCCCGCGACUUCUGGCAGCCCGUGAUCUGCCACGCGCGCCUCAAUCUCGACGGCCUGGUGGUCCGCAACAGCUCGGCACCCAUUACACUGAUGCUCGCUUGGAGCCCCGCGCCCACAGCUUUGGCCUCCGGUUCCAUCGCUGCCCUUGUAGGGAUCCUCCUCACUGUGGGCGCUGCGUACCUAUGCAAGUGCCUAGCUAUGAAGUCCCAGGCGUAAAGGGGGAUGUUCUAUGCCGGCUGAGCGAGAAAAAGAGGAAUAUGAAACAAUCUGGGGAAAUGGCCAUACAUGGUGGCUGACGCCUGUAAUCCCAGCACUUUGGGAGGCCGAGGCAGGAGAAUCGCUUGAGCCCAGGAGUUCGAGACCAGCCUGGACAACAUAGUGAGACCCCGUCUAUGCAAAAAAUACACAAAUUAGCCUGGUGUGGUGGCCCGCACCUGUGGUCCCAGCUACCCGGGAGGCUGAGUUGGGAGGAUCCUUUGAGCCCUGAAAGUCGAGGUUGCAGUGAGCCUUGAUCGUGCCACUGCACUCCAGCCUGGGGGACAGAGCACGACCCUGUCUCCAAAAAUAAAAUAAAAAUAAAAAUAAAUAUUGGCGGGGGAACCCUCUGGAAUCAAUAAAGGCUUCCUUAACCA